ACACAGACCGACACAGGCAGCGAGAGACACGAGGAGCAAAGCAAGUGAAGGCACAGACGCACGGGACAGGAGAGCCUGGGCAAGACUGGAGAGCCCAGACCUGGGAUGGCGGAUUCGUGCAGGAACCUCACCUACGUGCGGGGCUCGGUGGGGCCGGCCACCAGCACCCUGAUGUUCGUGGCCGGUGUGGUGGGCAACGGGCUGGCCCUGGGCAUCCUGAGCGCACGGCGACCGGCGCGCCCCUCGGCCUUCGCGGUGCUGGUGACCGGACUGGCGGCCACCGACCUGCUGGGCACCAGCUUCCUGAGCCCGGCCGUGUUCGUGGCCUAUGCGCGCAACAGCUCCCUGCUGGGCCUGGCCCGAGGCGGCCCCGCCCUGUGCGAUGCCUUCGCCUUCGCCAUGACCUUCUUCGGCCUGGCGUCCAUGCUCAUCCUCUUUGCCAUGGCCGUGGAGCGCUGCCUGGCGCUGAGCCACCCCUACCUCUACGCGCAGCUGGACGGGCCCCGCUGCGCCCGCCUGGCGCUGCCAGCCAUCUACGCCUUCUGCGUCCUCUUCUGCGCGCUGCCCCUGCUGGGCCUGGGCCAACACCAGCAGUACUGCCCCGGCAGCUGGUGCUUCCUCCGCAUGCGCUGGGCCCAGCCGGGCGGCGCCGCCUUCUCGCUGGCCUACGCCGGCCUGGUGGCCCUGCUGGUGGCUGCCAUCUUCCUCUGCAACGGCUCGGUCACCCUCAGCCUCUGCCGCAUGUACCGCCAGCAGAAGCGCCACCAGGGCUCUCUGGGUCCACGGCCGCGCACCGGAGAGGACGAGGUGGACCACCUGAUCCUGCUGGCCCUCAUGACAGUGGUCAUGGCCGUGUGCUCCCUGCCUCUCACGAUGAGGGGCAGUGUCUUUCGCCCAGUCACACAGAGCCAGGUCCUGGUCCUGGGUCCUUCCAUUGUAGAGCCUGAUCUCCCACCUACCUGGCUCCCCUCUGCCUCAGAGCAGGCCCCACCCUUGCCUCUGCACCUCGGUUUCCUGCGGGGACCCCGUCCUGCCCCUCCCCAAUGGGAGUGGCACAGACCCUGGUACCCACUCAGUGUCUGUGACACCUGGUCGUGCCACCUUUCUUCUGAGCUUCAGUUUCUGUUUCUGUAAAAUGCAAGAGGCCAGGCCGGAUUGGGGGGUCCUUAAAUCUUUUUUGGGGGUUACUCUGACUCAGAGACUCAGAUGCCGUGGACAGAUACACACAGGCACCACCGCAGCUCUGCGGCAGUUUCAGGGGGCCCAGCCGGGUGGCGCCACCUUCUUGCAGGGACGUUAUACUCAAAAAUCUGUGGAGCCCGAGGGUCCUCCCAGCUUCCAAGGGUGGGGGGACCCACAUACCUGGCCCCCAUCCCUCUCCCCUUAGGCAUCUCUGGCAAUUUCCUGGGGCUUUCUCUCCCUGUGUUCCCCAGAUACAUUUGUUACUUAGUCUUUAUCUUAUCUCCUUCCCCUCUGACAUGUCACCCCUACCUCAUCCCUGGUAAGCAAGUGGGAGGAGGGAGCCAGGGUGGGGAGGCUGAGGACUCCUGGGUGCUCCUUGACGCCCUCACCCUGCCCUCAGAUCCGCUGCUUCACCCAGGCUGUCGCCCCUGACAGCAGCAGUGAGAUGGGGGACCUCCUUGCCUUCCGCUUCUACGCCUUCAACCCCAUCCUGGACCCCUGGGUCUUCAUCCUUUUCCGCAAGGCUGUCUUCCAGCGACUCAAGCUCUGGGUCUGCUGCCUGUGCCUCGGGCCUGCCCACGGAGACUCGCAGACACCCCUUUCCCAGCUCGCCUCAGGGAGGAGGGACCCAAGGGCCCCCUCUGCUCCUGUGGGAAAGGAGGGGAGCUGCGUGCCUUUGUCGGCUUGGGGCGAGGGGCAGGUGGAGCCCUUGCCUCCCACACAGCAGUCCAGCGGCAGCGCCGUGGGAACGUCGUCCAAAGCAGAAGCCAGCGUCGCCUGCUCCCUCUGCUGACAUUUCAAGCUGACCCUGUGAUCUCUGCCCUGUCUUCGGGCGACAGGAGCCAGAAAAUCAGGGACAUGGCUGAUGGCUGCGGAUGCUGGAACCUUGGCCCCCAAACUCUGGGGCCGAUCAGCUGCUGUUUCUCCUGCGGCAGGGCAGUCGCUGCUGGCUCUGGGAAGAGAGUGAGGGACAGAGGAAACGUUUAUCCUGGAGUGCAGAAAGAAUGGUUCUCUCAAAAUAACCAGUGGCCUGGCCGACCUGCUCUGGCCCUGGAUUCCCCAUCCAUCUCAUUGUCUAAAUAUUUAGAAGGCGGAGAAGUUCCCAGAGGCUUCUGUACAGUCAGGUCUGCUCUGGUCUGGGUGCUGGCUCCAAUCUGCGUCCACUUAGGAGGCCCAACUGCCCACCCCAAGUCCCCAGGGGAUGGCCCUCCCCCUCUACCAAGCCACUCCAAGAGCCAGCCCCUUUCUGCUCCACAAAAACCACAGUUAUUGGAAAAGCUCCCUGCCUUCCCUUGCCGCUGGUCCCCCACCAGGCUUGGGAGCCCUGGCAUCCCAAAGGGGCAACGGGAGGAAGGGGAGGCUGCUGCAUUGUGGGUGAUGACGUAGGACAUGUGCUUGGUACAAAAAGGGCCUGAGACAUUCCACCUAGCUUGACUGGCUGCAAGAUGAGAACUGGGGGGGUGCAGGUGGUGGGGAGACAGAUGGAGAAGCUGGCAGAUGAAGGGUGGGGGCUGCGGAUCCCAGGGACUGCCCCAGAACACAAACCUAAGUCCUGUGCCUGUCCCCAGGGUCCUGAAUAAAUAAAAGCCUCCUUGCAGAGCCUGA